AUGAGAAAGAGCACCAGGCUACCAGGUCCAAAGACUUUCUCAACUUCCCUUUCUCCUCCCAGCAGCGUCCAAAAUUCUUGGCUGCAAACUCACCUGCGUGGGCGCACGAUUUUAUCUCACUCGAGUUCUCCUCGCGAAGACCCAGCCCAGCGGCGGGGUUUGACUCAGCACAUAGGCACGGUCCCUGAAAUCAGAUCGUGGCUCUCGAGCUACGAGCGACCCACCCCCGCCCCACCCUCCGUCACCCAGGCGGCAGCCGCAGAGGCAGCUGCGGCGCUCCAACCCGACAAGCGUCCCAAGGAGGUGCAGCCCCGGGGAAGCUGGCGACCCUCCCGAGCUGGGAGAAAGACAAACUUCCUCUCGCCCGCACUGCCCCCACGUCCACCGCUGCCCUGGGGGCCCCCUUCGAAGGCGAGGUCACGGCCCGUUUGGUGGUGGCUUGACCGGGGCGUCCCAGAGGAGCCAGCAAGCCCUCGCCUCCUCUGUGGGGUGUUUGCCAAGGACAGCUGGGCUCUGCGCUGCUUGCAGCCGCUGCUCCAGGAAGUCGGCCCCAAGCAGGCUUGCAGGAUUCACUAUAGAAUCCCUGCCUUUCCCCAGAGCCUGCCGGUGUUCUGCGCAGGGCCCUGCCUCGCCUUCCCACGGAGGGACGCGAAGACCCCGGGGUCUCUUCUUUCAGUUUCGCUCCAAGGUGCAGCCGCUUUCCCGGCAGCGGGACGUCUUUUAAUUGGGGACAUGUAUAUGGAUGAGGAUGGCACUCCGCCAGCAAGCCCCAGGUGGGAAGCAUGCCCUCCGGAGGGAGCUGUGCCUAGAACGUCGAAGACAGCAGGAGGAGCUGAAGGCUCUGACAAGGCCGUCAUGUAAAAACAGCAUUAAGGAUCAUGACCUUUUCCCUCGAAUGGACCCAUUUUCGUCUUUUAAUUCCACAAUCAGAGGGAAUGAGCAAUGAAGGGGGAGGAAGGCUGCCUUAUGCGUUCUAGGAUGUUUAGCACCUGCAUACACACAUCCAUAGGGACAGCCAAAUGUCUCCAGACAUUGCUAAAUGCCCCUUGCCAGGGAGUGGCAAAGUCAAAGUCAGAACCUCUGCCUCAAAGGAAGAACAUGGAUCCCCUUUAUCUGUACAUUCUAGGGGCCUAGCACAAGCCCUCUGUGCUGAAAACAUCUCUGAAUUAUCCCAAUCGCCACAUCGAUGCAAUCAUUUUAAAGAUGAAGCAAUUCUGCUGUCUGGAGGACCUAUGCUUCCCCAAGGCCAUAAAAGAGUUGGCAUAGCACCCUAAAUAAUGUGUUUUGUGGGCGGCCUCUCCACCCCCGAUGUGUGCUACUUGACCUGCUUGUUGGCACUGGUGGAGAAACUCCUAACUCGUUUCCUCAUUAGUGCACUGCAUUCAGCUGAAGGACCUAGCUGACCUUUCAUCUGUCCCACAACACUCACAGGAGUAGCGUAAUGGGGAUGGUGGGUCUUGCUAUUUUGUCCAGGUUGGGCUGAACUUGUGAUCCUUCUGCCUCAGCCUCCUGAGUAGC